CUAGAUUCUUCUUGACCUGUCUGAGCAUGCACUUCUUCCUUUUGGCUAUGUGGCAGGGCCCUCUCUGGAAUGAGGAUCUUAUGACCUUCAGUUAAACAAGGUAGGUAAGAUAAUUUCUUUAUGGCCAGUUUUUACACAGAAAAGCAGAAGAAAAAUUAGAGUAAUAUUUUCAGAUUUUAUGGCUGGCUUUGGGGAAAAGGAAUUGUGGUUUCUAUAACCCACGUUGGGGAACAGGGAUUCUAGUUUCUUAUAGCUAGCCUCAGGGGAAAAUGAGACUGAGAGGCUGAAGGUCAGAAGAUGAGAGGAAAAACUUUUACUUCUGAGGUUUUUUUUUUUUUUUUUUUUUUUUUUUUUUUUUUUUUUUGGGGAGGAGGGGAGUAUUGUUUUCUGAGUCUCAACAGUACAUAGAAACUUACAGCACUCUGGAAAGUCAAUGCCUACCCUGUCUCCGCCCUGUUCAAGGUUACUGGAAUGUGGUUCCUGCUCAGCCUGAUAUCUUCCCAGAUAUCUGAGAAUUGGGAAAGUAAUUUCUCUGUCCUUGAGUUUUCCCACACCAAUCUGGAUAUUUCUAAAGCCACAACCCCUCACCCUACAUCUUCAGGGUGGGAACAGUAAAAAUGUUUCUGGUGUCUUUCUUGAGCUCUUCUACCCCUUUCCCGUAAUUCUCCAAGCCAAAGAGAAUAGGAUUUUCUUCUACUUUACCUACUUCAUAGCCACCACCUUCCUUAUAUCAAUCUCUGACUAAAUCCUUCAUACUGGACUAAGAUACCUUGUCUUUACUAUGGGAGAAACCCUAUCAUUUGGUCCACCAGGCCUAGCCUUGAUAUGUUGAACCAUAAACAAAUUUACAUUUUAUGUCUUGACAAUGCCUCGAUUUGAAGCCUAAAAACUCGAUUUAAAAAAUCCUAUAUUUAAUAUCGAAAGUUAAAAAGUAAAUAUUUCUUUUGUAUUUUUUAUACAAGAAUCCAAAUCCUCAGCAGAAAGGUGCCUUGGAUUGAUUAAGUUGUAUACCCAGAAAGUGACAUUAAUACACUUCUUGAAACAUUACCCUUUCCGAUUACACAAAUAUUCUAGCCGACAAAUCUGAUCAUGCUAAUUUCCUAUUUAAAGCCUUUUUAAUAAUUUCUCAUUCCCUUAAGAUAAAAUCAUUUUGGAGAUCUUCCUGACCAUCUAACCUAGGUUAUAAACCUCGUGCGUGCUUCUACAAGCUCCCAUACUUCCUCUUUCUUAACACCCAUCCUACUUUUACUUUUUCAAUAUAUAUCUUUCUUGAUAAAUUUGAACUCCAAAUUUUCAACACAUAGCACAGUGUCCUGGACAUAGGUGCUUCAUAAAUAUUUGCAUGAGUUUGAAUUAAAUGCAUGUCGUAUUUCUUACUUGAAAAUCAGUAAAUUGUUAUUCUAGUUUACACAGUUCCUUUUUUUUGAGAUUUAUAAAUUUGAGACUACUCUAAAAAAUGAACCCACUGUUGGGCUUACAAUACCAAUUUCUAGUUCUACAGAGCCAGGCUUUCGAACACAGAAAAUUCACCAGUAAGUACUUUCUUGUCAUAUCCUUUGACAGGUAAUAAUUUACCCUCUCCUUGGGGACACCCCUACCUUAAGACAAGAAUUCUUUCAAACUUCAAAAACAUCCAUCUUCAUUAAUAAGUUCAUAAUGAAGACUUUUCACUUUAAGAUGCCUAAUUAUCUUUCACAGAUAUUUAUGAAAUUUCAAUUGUGCCAAGAUUUUUCACAGGCUUAUUUUACUUUAAGCUGGUCCUUCCAUUUAUUGAAGCUUCAAUUAAUUAGACUUCAUCAUGUUAUAGCUAAAUGGAUGUGACUAGAAAGAGCAGCAUACAGACAUCUAUGUGUAAACUGUUACUUGUUGGUUAACAUUUAUGUUUGAAAUGGAAAAUCAAUAAAAGGGAACUUAUAUUAAUUUAUAAGCACAUUAAGAAAAGAGGGGACACUAUUUUUGAUCCCAAGAUAGCAACAAAACUAAAAACUUUUCCAAAGAAGCAAACGGGAACAGAGGUCAAUAGGCUGUGACCUCUAUUUUAUGUUUAAAACGUUUGCACAUCCACUAAGUGCACUGCAGAAUCUUAAAUGCAAUUAAAAUCAAUGGGCAUACAAGUUAUAGAGUAGCUUGAGGAAGCACAAGUCAAUCUUCAUUAGCUAUUGUAGCAAAGAUUCCUUCCAAAUCCAUGGGAGCAGGUGCUGUUUAUACUCCCUUCAUUGACGCCCAGAACAAUGGCAUAGGGUGAGCAUUGAAUACUUAUUUGCUACGCGCAUGAAUGAAUGAAGCUACGCUGCGAAGGCAGACUGCGUGGCUGCUGGUCCCGUGGCUGCUGGCCCCGCAGCAUGUCUGCCGCCUUUUCAGCAGGCUUGCUGCAUCUCCUCAUUCCCUCACCUUUCUGGCAGUAAGGAGUUCCCACGUUUGCCCCGCUUCAGUGUCGUGGACUGGCAAAAUGCUGUCUCUAAACCCCUCCACGCCUCAGUUGUUUUUGAAGAACUUACAUCCAAACAGACAAGAAAAGGAUAAAAGCACCAUUGGUUCAUGGCAAGUUAUUACAUUUUAAGUGAUUAACUGGAACAAAUCACAAGACAGUGGCAUAGCAGAGAUGGAAGAACUUCCUGUACCACAUAACAUCAAAAUAAGCAAUAUAACGUGUGACUCAUUCAAGAUUUCAUGGGAAAUGGAUUCAAAAUCAAAGGAUCGCAUUACACACUAUUUUAUUGACCUCAACAAGAAAGAGAACAAGAACUCCAAUAAAUUUAAACACAAGGAUGUUCCCACAAAAUUGGUGGCAAAAGCUGUUCCCUUGCCUAUGACUGUCCGUGGACACUGGUUUUUAAGCCCAAGAACUGAAUAUACAGUAGCAGUGCAGACUGCCUCAAAACAAGUUGAUGGUGAUUAUGUUGUGUCUGAAUGGAGUGAAAUUAUAGAAUUCUGCACCGCAGACUAUUCAAAAGUUCAUCUAACACAAUUGUUGGAGAAGGCUGAAGUGAUUGCAGGACGCAUGCUUAAGUUUUCUGUUUUUUAUCGUAAUCAGCACAAAGAAUAUUUUGACUAUGUUCGAGAACAUCAUGGGAAUGCUAUGCAGCCAUCUGUCAAGGAUAACAGUGGUAGCCAUGGCUCUCCUAUCAGUGGAAAAUUAGAAGGCAUCUUCUUCAGCUGCAGCACUGAAUUCAAUACUGGAAAGCCACCCCAGGAUUCACCUUAUGGAAGAUACAGGUUUGAGAUUGCCGCAGAAAAACUUUUUAACCCCAAUACUAACUUAUACUUUGGGGACUUCUACUGUAUGUACACUGCUUAUCAUUAUGUGAUUCUUGUUAUUGCUCCUGUGGGAUCACCAGGAGAUGAAUUUUGUAAGCAGCGCCUUCCUCAACUAAAUUCUAAGGAUAAUAAAUUUUUGACCUGUACAGAAGAAGAUGGGGUGCUGGUUUACCACCAUGCCCAGGAUGUCAUUUUAGAAGUCAUUUACACUGACCCUGUGGAUCUUUCUGUGGGCACCGUGGCAGAAAUCACUGGUCAUCAGCUCAUGAGUUUGUCUACUGCAAAUGCAAAGAAAGAUCCCAGCUGCAAAACCUGUAAUAUCAGUGUUGGACGUUAAUGCCCACUUUUCUUAUUCUUACUCAGCCCCUUUUCCUCCCUUAGGAGCAUUGGUCCUCUGUUGUCCAUUUUUAUCACCAGAUGUUUUCCACUGAAGCAUGCACAUGCCACUGUCACCAAAACAAACAACUACCACUUUCCAAAUUUCAUUCAGAACCAUUUUAGUGUUUUCCUAUUCCCUACCCCUCCCACUACUUUCAAUGAUGAAAUACCCUAAGUUAAGUUCUCCUUUUGACACUUUAUUGCCUAGAUGCUGCAAUGUUUUUAUGUUUCCUUUAUGCCAAACAUAACAAAACAGUUAUAUAGACUGCUUUAGCAAAGUACACAAUAAUGGCUUAUAAAUGGUGUUUAAAUAUGCAUUCAUUUUAAUCUACUGAACAAAUAUUGGGAUAACUCCAAACCGCAUGAAAGGGUGUAAUUGCAGCAUGAGUUAAAUCUUGAAGCCUAGAAUUGUCAGCACUUCCAACUUCUUGUUUGACAGUGUUAUUUAUGUUAUUUAUAUUAGCUAACAGGAAACAACUACUGUGUUUCAACAUAAUAAAUAUAAUAGAAAAAUAUUUUAUUUGUAUUGUUGUAUAAAAUAUUUACAAUCAUAUAGAAUAUAUAGAGUUACAUUUUAAUAGCAACUGUGUACAUGUCACGAAACCAUUUCCCUUAUCAAAGAUGUAAUUUGUAAACCUCAAAUAGUUGUGUAUCUGUCCUGUUAGAAGUAGAUGACUUCAAUUAAACAAAUUUAUGAAGGACAUUAUUCUGAUUCAUAAAAGUUAUAAAAUAUUAGGUAAAUACAGAGAAAACAAUAAGCCUCUGAAAUAAGUCUGUUUCUGAAAUAGUCAAUAGUCUUCCCAUCCAAACUAUAAGAGAAUGUGAAUUUCUUCAACAUCAUACUUAAACAUUACAGAAAAUAGAAAUACAAACAAGGUUGGUACAUGAGAGAAAAUGUUGACCUUUUACUUCCUUUUACAAAAAUGAAAAUAAUAAACAUGUUUUCGUAUAAAAUAACACAAAAUGAUAUACACUGAAGUUGAUGAAGCAAAUAAAUAUUCUGGCUUCUUUUUCAAGGUAUCAGGGCAAACAAUUUCCAAACUUUUCAUUUUGUACAGAAGGAUGAAUAACUACAGCUCAUGGGAAAUGUUUUGACUUUACAAAGUAUAGAUGUUGGAACAUUAAGAAAAAUGUAUAUUCCCAAUGAAAAAAUAGUUAUAUCAUCUUAUAGUAAACCAAAAGAUUAGCAAUAAUACUAUGGACACAUUAGAUUAUAUACUACAGACACAUAUCUAUCCAAAAUACCUAUUUUAAAUUUUUAAUACAAUAUUUUAUUUUAAUAUAAACAUCUGUCAGUUAUAGACAAAGAUAAUAAUUCACAAAGUACAUGCUAUCAGAAUGAACUUUGGUAACCAGAAAUGUAAAAUUUCAAAUAACGGAUAAAAUAAUGUGUUAUUUUUAUAGAGAAAGAAAAAAAUAGCAACACAAUCUAGUUUAUUUUAGGGUACUGAGAGCCUAGCAGACUUAAAGGACAAGGUAGUAAAUGUUUUAUCACUCAAAAAUCCAUUAGAAGUUUCAAAUAAAUUGCUUUCUUGCUAGCUGUAUUCCUUCCUACUUGAAAAGCGAAUUUCUUUUCCUCCUAUGAUUGAUUUUUUAAAAUCAUGCUCUUUUCCAUACAUCAACAUAAACAGUCUUUGGAUACUAAAUAAACUUUCCCUAACAAGUGUCCUAGCUAUGUUAUUUAGAUUUGAUAAAAUAUUAGACAUUUUUAAAAAUACUUGUAUUGACUAUGAGUUUUCUGCUUGGCAUGGAGGACACUGAAUUUUUUCCCAAUUAUAUGGCUACCUGUUGUAUUCUUCCCCCCGUUUAAAUCCCUUCUCCUUGUAUAUAAUUAAACUUGCUAUUCCUUCUUAAAAACAGCUAAUACUACCACUAAAGUGCUUCCAUUUUCAUUGUGUCAAAACUACUUAGCAAGGAUGGCAGAGGAAAAUAAACUUUACUUUAUAUCAUGGGUGAAAGUGAUCAUAACAUUUCCUGAACCUCAAAUAGUUUUGGCCACAUCUUGCUUGCUGAUGAGGACCUCUAAUAGUCUCAGUUUGGCUUUUAUGUGCUUAUAUUCAUAAUACUCAUCUGCCAUUGGUAUCCUAUCUUCCUUUUGUGGACUUCUGCAAAACAAAAAUACAUUUGUUAGUUCACAA